AGUUGCCGGUGAGCUUGGGAGAACCGUGGGCGCUGAGGCGGUGAGUCCCCGAGCGGCCAGAGGGCGUGGCCGUUCCCUGGGGCGCGGGCGCGGGUAGCGGGGCUCCUUUCCGUGGCCGGGGCCAUGCUAACUGGGUGAUUCCAGCUGUGCCCCGGGCGGCGGGCGCCGGAAGGAGUGGUGGGCGGUGGGCCCCUAUCCGGCCAGGGUCCCCGCCACCACUCCCUGCGACCCGACCGGGCCUUCCCGGGAGUCCUUCUGGGCUGGGAGCUCCCCUCCAGGCGUCGGGGCCUCGUCGCCCAAGAGCGAACAGGGGCCGCGCCCGAGACACUAGCAUCCGAAUUUGAAUCAGCUUUUACACUUUUUAGGGACGUGUCACUCUUGCCGUUCCUCAAGUGCUCUCUUUACACACAUCGCUUUUCUUAUAGGCCCCAUGAGGGUGGAUUCCCUACGAGAAGGUUUGGAGAGAAAUCACUGGUCCCACAGUGAAAUGAACGUUUCUCUGGGAAGGGUCCAUCGAAGGAAACCCGAAGGGUCAAUUCCCUGGUAGACGUGGUGGAAGGUUUUGGGUCAGUCAGGGAAGGGCUGACCAGCUGUGAGGCUGGCGCAGAUUAACGGGUGGGUCCAGAGCCAAAAACAGCACAGUUCCUGGAUGCCCUCCAGCAACGGUUAGGUGCCUAGACUCUGGGAAAUAGAGGCCCCCUAGGAAUGACUCCUGACAAGCAAUAAACUUUAAUUGAGUGCUUCCUCUGUGCCGGGCAUGCUGCUAUUCGCUUCGCAUGCAAUUGGAUCCAUGCAGAACAUUUUAUAAAGUAGAUGCUAUGAUUAUCUUCUGUUACAAAAGAGGCACUGGGUGUCAGGGUCACACAGCUAGCAGGUUAUUAUACCUAAACCGAUCUGCUAAAGUCGGGCUACCAUCAUGGUAAAGGGGGAUACAAGGACAGAGUGCUGAUUUAGGUUGACUGGGGAGGAAGAGAGUCAUGAGUACUUUUUUUCCCUUGAAUCCCCUCCAGAGAAGAGGACAACUACAGCAGCUGUCUCAGCACAUGCAGAGAGAGAGGACCCAAGGCACAUGGGCAGAUACAGGUCUUGAGACCUGUAGAAACAUCUGUAGGUGGCUCCCUCCCACCCCAACGAUUUCAGAGAGAAACAAGUCGGAAUCUGAGAAGUGAGGCUCCAGAUAAACUGUAAACUGCUGGAAGGGGGCGAUGGCUGUGGCCCUGGGUUGUGCAAUCCAGGCAUCCUUGAAUCAAGGCUCUGUGUUUCAAGAAUAUGAUACUGACUGUGAAGUUUUCCGUCAGCGCUUCAGGCAGUUCCAGUACAGAGAAGCAGCUGGGCCUCAUGAAGCAUUUAACAAACUCUGGGAGCUUUGCUGUCAAUGGCUGAAGCCAAAGAUGCGCUCUAAGGAACAAAUCCUGGAGCUGCUAGUGUUGGAGCAAUUCCUAACUAUCCUGCCCACAGAGAUAGAGACCUGGGUGAGGGAGCACUGCCCAGAGAAUAGAGAAAGAGUUGUGUCACUGAUAGAAGACUUACAGAGAGAACUUGAGAUACCAGAGCAGCAGGUAAGAAAAGAAUGUGGGAUCUUUGUGAUUGGUCCAAAGGAAGUAGCUGAGGCAGCUGGGACUAGACCACACAUUUGUCUCUAUGUCAUUCCCCAGCCUCAAGAUUUCUCCAGAGUCCUCUUCCUUUUUCUCUUCUGCUGAACUCAGCAAAUGAGUCAGUGCUUUUAACUCUAUCAGACUCAAUUCCCCUUCUAUAACAAAUAGUUUAUAAUGUCCACUUUACUAUGCACAAAUGAAAUUGAUAGACAACAUAAUCUACCCACAUACAUCAACCCAAAGCAUCAGUAAAUUGCUCCAUGGCCUGAAGGCCAAUUCUAGCCAUACCCUGUUUAUCUGUAUACUCUGUAUGUAAUGGUUUUUUUAUCUUGUUGAAAGGUCAUUGAAAAAAAGAGGAAGGAGAAGAACUGACAGUGAAUGUGCCCCACAGUGCCUAAAAUAUUUACUAUUUGGCUCUUUAUAAAGUUUGCCAACCCUGAAUCAAGUCUAGAAGGAAUAUAAAGGAAAAGAAACAUAGUUUGUUAUAAAUUGAUAGGGAUUUGUACAUAUAUGUGCUUGGGCCUGACCGAAUGUCAUGAAGUUGUCAGAUGUUUGCAUCUAUGCUUAGAAUCAUUGUGAAUGGGACAGCCAGAAAUUCAGACUGAUAAAGCUCAAGUACUACGAACAGUGUUGCUCCUCGUCAUGUGAUUUUCCAAAAUGGCAUACGACUCUAGACAUUUGCUGCUGAAUACAGUCACUACUAGUCAUGUACAGCUCUUGAGCCCUUGAAAUAUGGCCAAUACAAAUUGAGAUCUGCUGUAAGUAUGAAAUACACACCACAUGCAGAAGACUUGGUAUGAAAAAAGUUGAUAUGCAUGACAUGCUCUUGGAAGAACUGGCACCAGUGGGAACGGCACACAUACCACCAACCAUGCACCUAGAGUCACCUGCACUCCAGGUAAUGGGACCUGCCCAGGAGGCCCCAGUAGCAGAGGCAUGGAUCCCACAGGCAGGGCCACCGGAGCUGAACUAUGGUGCUACUGGAGAAUGUCAGAACUUUCUGGACCCUGGAUAUCCAUUACCAAAACUUGACAUGAACUUCUCAUUGGAGAAUAGAGAAGAGCCAUGGGUGAAGGAAUUACAGGAUUCUAAAGAAAUGAAACAAUUACUUGAUUCCAAGAUAGGUUUUGAGAUCGGGAUAGAAAAUGAAGAAGAUACUUCAAAACAGAAAAAAAUGGAGACUAUGUAUCCAUUUAUUGUAACUUUAGAGGGGAAUGCUCUCCAGGGUCCCAUUUUGCAAAAAGACUAUGUACAGUUAGAAAAUCAAUGGGAAACCCCCCCAGAGGAUUUACAGACAGAUUUAGCAAAACUGGUAGAUCAGCAGAACCCCACUCUGGGAGAGACACCUGAGAACUCCAACUUGGAAGAACCUCUCAACCCUAAACCCCACAAGAAAAAGAGUCCAGGAGAGAAACCUCACCGAUGUCCUCAGUGUGGAAAAUGUUUUGCUCGGAAGUCACAACUUACUGGGCAUCAGAGAAUUCAUUCAGGAGAAGAACCUCACAAAUGCCCUGAAUGUGGGAAAAGAUUCCUUCGUAGUUCAGACCUUUAUAGACACCAACGACUUCAUACAGGGGAGAGACCCUAUGAAUGCACUGUAUGUAAAAAGCGAUUCACUCGGCGGUCACAUCUUAUAGGGCACCAGAGAACCCAUUCUGAAGAAGAAACAUAUAAAUGUCUUGAGUGUGGGAAAAGUUUUUGUCAUGGAUCAAGUCUUAAAAGACAUCUGAAAACUCAUACAGGUGAAAAACCUCAUAGAUGUCAUAAUUGUGGGAAAAGUUUUAGUCGACUGACAGCUCUUACUUUGCACCAGAGAACGCAUACUGAAGAGAGACCUUUUAAAUGUAAUUAUUGUGGGAAAAGUUUUAGACAGAGACCAAGCCUCGUUAUUCAUUUAAGAAUCCACACAGGGGAGAAGCCAUACAAGUGUACUCAUUGUUCUAAAAGCUUCAGACAGAGAGCCGGCCUUAUUAUGCACCAGGUCACUCACUUUAGAGGACUUAUUUAAGAAUUGCUAAGGGAAACAGGUCUUACACAAAUUGACACUAACUCAAAAAAAAUCUUAACCUGCAGCAGGCUGUUUGUCUUGGAAGCUUUUGUUUGAGCUUAUAAGAACAUAGACAGCUUUUUUUUUUACUAGUUUUAAAACCCAUCUUCCAAGGUAUAUGAAUUCUAGAGUAUUUAUCUACUCCUGUGAUUUUCUUAGAUUUGAUUUCUUCUGUCUGCACAACUCUUCUUUUUUUAAUUACAAUGAAAAAUUUUGUGUUCCAAGGCAACUGUAUCAUAGGUGUAAACAUAAAGCAUAUAAAUUAUGACAAUCCUUUUAGAGGUAGGGUCAAUAUAGUGGAUAAACCUGUCUAUCAGACGUAUUGAUUAUAGCAGUACUAUAGUUAUUCUGCUGUCAUUAUUAAAGAUGAUUAUAUUCAUUCAAAGCUUUAGAUGUGUCCCAUGUGGCAAGAAAGGAGACAGUGAAUUUUGUCAAACAAUAAAAAUGUGUCAGGAACACAAGGAUGAAGGGGAUGUCAUUUGCCUGGUAAGAACUGGGUUAUUUCCACUGAAAUUUGUUAUGUUUAAGGAAAUUAAGAUUUUAAGCUUGAAAUUAUACAAGCAGAAUCUAAUUUAAUUUUGAUUGACUGAAGAACCAGGGUCUUUUGCUCUCCUUUGGUAUUUCACUCUCCUUUGGUAUUCAAUCAUGUGUCUUUUAGUGCUUUUUAAAAUUUUACCCAUUCUUUAAUUCAGCAUCUCCCUAUGUAUGUGUCAUAGAAUACUUAGUUCUGCUAGAUAUUCUGCAAAUAUAUUUGGGAAUUACUUCCUGCUGUUUCGCCUUCUUAGGUUCAUAGUACACAUCAGCAUAUGAGAAUCUCUGAGAGGUCCUCUAGAAAGGAGAGAAAAAGCACCUCUUUUGGCUCAAUGUUUUCCAAACUUAUUUGACCCCAAAACCUUUUUCAUAUACCCAAUAAUAAGCUACAGAACUAAUAUUCUGCAAAUGUCUCUUGGAACACACUGCCUUAAACAGAUAUUUCUAUAGCUGUCAGUAUAGUUAUGUUGCUCCCAAGCCUAGUUAUCUCCAGUUGUUUUAAGGGUGUUAUGAAAAAUUCUUAAAAUAUAUAUGAAUUUGUGUAACACACACAGAGACACACACACAUACUACUUUAAGGGGGUGAGGAUCAUUAAUUCAGAUAAUUUUUAAGUUUCCUAGUGAUUCUCAAUCUCUUUGAAUUUUACUUACAUUUACACACACACGCACACACAUAUGUAUAUACACAUAUCAUUUUAAGAAGCUGAGGAUCACUAAUUCAGAUAAUGUAUAAGUUUCCCAGUGAUUCUCAACCUCUUUGAAUUUUACUUAUAAUUACAUACACACACACACUGCUACUUAUAUAAAUGUUCUCAUGUAAUCAUGGUAACAGCUCAAAUUCCCAAAGCAAGGGAAGACUUCUCAUUGUCAGUUAAACCUGUUAAAACAUGAAAAUAUUCAUUGAGCCUAGUUCCUUGUUAUAAAAUACAAGAAAUAAGACAUUCAGGCAUUUUCCCUUUAUGAAGAUGUUCAGUCAUCCUUUCCUUGAACUACAAUUAGGAAAAGUAUAUGUCUUUAUUCCAUUGAAGUUCUCGAGAGUGAUAUAAAUACUUUGGGGGGUAUCUACUAUGUGCCUAACUAGUCCUGUUCUAGGCUUAGUGGAAGCUAGUAAAGAAAUAUAAUUCAUGGAUCAGGCUCAUAAAGAUUUUAUAAUAUUUUUAGUUAAACAAGAGUUGGGAAACAGGUGGAGAAUAAUGCAAGAGAGUUUGUAAUUAAGUGCCAAUUAUACCAAUUGCUAGACCCAGGAUGUAUCUUUAAUUCUUGUCAUCCAGGUCAACAUAUGAUGCUGCUAUAAGUCUGGGGCUCAAAUUGAUAUCCCAGUAGCAAUAAACAUAUAAUAUAGGAGGAGUCUGAAUGUAGAGAUGAAAAAUACAGAAUGUAAUGGCUUCUCUUUUCUCUCUUGUGGAAUUGCAUUCAAACCAGAACAGUGCCUUAGAAUGGAUGUGCCCAACUGCUCUGUAUUUAUGCAAUAUUUGAAUAAAGCGGAAAUGUAUGUGCUCUUCCUGCUUCACUUGCACUAAUUAAUUAUUUGAACAACUUAGAGCUUCUUCCCUGAACAGUGGCAACAAGCAUGGCAAUUGACUCUGUCCUCAUCCCAAGUUGGAAUCGCUUUUCUCUCUGCAACCAUGGCACUGUGAUUAUGCAUCAUUUUUAGCAUUUAAUACAGUCCAUUUUUGGCUAGUAGGGUUAGUUGCAAUCAUAAUAUGAGUUGCAUCCUCCCUCUCAUUUAUAUCAAAUAUACUUGACUAGAUUUUUACAAGUUAGAGA